AGGUGUCACACACUUUUAAACAACCAGAUCUCAUGAGAACUCCCUAUCCCAAGGACAGCACCAAGACAUGAGGGAUCCACCGCCACGGCCUGAACACCCCCACCAGGCCCACCUCCAGUCCUCCAGUGUUGGGGAUGACAUUUCAACAUGAGAUUUGAGGGACAGAUAUCUGAACUAUAGCACCACCAUGCCAGUUCCCUUUCUUUCUGUCAUCCCAGAUCUACCAUGAAUCAUGUGUCACAUCAAAUUAGACUCGUUAGGGCAUAAGCAGGGGCCCCGCAGUCCAGAAUGUUCCAAAUAAAUUGAGACUUGUCCAUCUGUGUGUCCUGAUUUGGGGGUUCAAAGAAUAGUCCCUCUAGACAGGGGCACAAACCCUUCCUUCACACACAGUAGGCCCUUGAGGAAUAGUGGUUGCAGCAAUAAAGAAGAGAAGAGAAUUCUCAAGGGUGUAUGUGGCCUCUCCCCCUAAGAGAUUUUGACUCUGCAAUCCAACCUCAACCACACGGGAGAGAGGGCAGCCAGUGCUGAGGCUGGAUGGGGGCUUCAUACCUGUGUCAUCAUGGGUGCCGGGGCCCAGCCUGCCCUGUGCUAGGGUCACUUCCACACCAUCUCUGUACCCGCCACCAGUCUCCAAUUUGGCCCACAUUGCACUUUCAGCCUUGCUCUGGCCCUGCCAAGCUUUUCGUAAUGGGGUCACUUUGGCCAUGGCCUCACCCCUCUGGAUGUCAGGACAACGCAGCCAGACAGGGUAAUCAGACUUAGGCAAAAUGGUGUGUGUGUGUGUGUGUGUGUGUGUGUGUGUGUGUGUGUGUGUGUAGGGGGAGGGAGCAUUCAACAGGGAGAGAAUACCAGAUAAUAAAGAGCUACAGAGCCAACAGGGACAUGGAGCCACUCCCACUAACUGAACCUCCCUCCUCUUUCCCUCCAUCCUUGGAAGUUGCGUUCCAGCCAGCUGCCACUGUUAAUUCAUAUGAGAGAUUGGACCAGGGAGAUGCCACCAGGCUUUCACCCCCGCUGUGAUGCUGAGGCUGUGGGAGGGAUGGUGUGGUUGACUGGGGCCACCUUCAUUAGACAGAGCUGCCAUCCUGAUAAAGGAAAGGCUUCUUGUCUCAGAGCUGUGUCCUCCCACUGGCUUUUCUCCCUGCAUGCUGUAACUGGUCAUCUCAGUCCUGAAGCAGGUAUGUGUGUUGGGCCAAGGUGGAAGGAGAGUGACACUGUUAUUAAAUUAACCCAGUCCCUUUCAUUGCAUCCUCCAAGUGAAGAACAAAAGGGAUUUUGCAUUUGCCCACAGUGUCUCUCUAAGCAAGGUCUCUGGAACAUCUGUAGGAACUCAGAGACGUUUGGAAUGGGCCAAUAAAACAUGGUGAGCAUCCAGCAGCAGCCUGGGGUGCUGGGCAGAGCCGGGACCUGGGUAGGAAUCACAGCAGGAUUCCAGCCCUGGCUCUGCGCCUUGCAUUGCUCUCACCUGGCUUCCAUAUCUGGAGGAACAUACCUAUUUCUCACGAUCACUGUGAAGAUGGAAUGGGGUUUUGUAUUUGAAGCUCUGUGUGCAGUUCUGGAGCCCCGAAUGUCCUUGGGGGUGCUCUGAAACCUUAGUGCCUUUAUCUCUUCUAAUGGUAGGAAAUGCACCCUUAUUUUAGUCAGAUCCUGUGAAUUAAAUUUUAAAAUGGCCAUAAUAGCUAAGAAGGUAAACUAUUAGUGACUAACUAAGUUGAAGUCUCCAUCAGUGUCAAGAAGACAGUUUCAUUUGCUGUUACAUAAAGUUUUCAGAUUGUUUUUCUCAUACUUCCAACCCAAACGUGCAGAAUAUUUAAAGCUUAGCAAAAAAAAUUAUAGGGAACUUAGAAAUAUAUAAAACAUGUGAUGAUUGUAAUUUUCUUGUGUUAACUGGGUUUGCAACUAUUUUGCUAGGAUAAUCUGCCCAAUUAACCUCUCAUAUAACUUCUGAAACUUGUUUCAUAGAACACGUAAGGGCAAAGGAAAAGCAAGACUCAGUCAAUGUCUGAAGCAAACUGGAGUCAAUGAGGCAAUGCCUGCUUAGAACUUUGCACGCUUGAAGUUUCAUACUGUUAAUUAAAUCUGCCUCAAUUCUUUUUUGAGGGACAAAUGGGAUUCACCAUGGGAAAGAGAGUUAUCUGAGAGGAACAUCCCAGAUUGGAGAAGGAAGAGGUCAACUCAGCCCAACUAGAGUAGUCCAACAGUUUAAUUCUAUCUCACUACAACAUAAGCGUUCUGUCAGGAACGAGUGGAAUAUCUCUUUCUCAUAAUUUUUACGGUGGAAGCGUUUUUAAAAGUAAUCGCCUAUGGACUCCUCUUUCACCCCAAUGCCUACCUCCGCAACGGCUGGAACCUACUAGAUUUUAUAAUUGUGGUUGUGGGGCUUUUUAGUGCAAUUUUAGAACAAGCAACCAAAGCAGAUGGGGCAAACGCUCUCGGAGGGAAAGGGGCCGGAUUUGAUGUGAAGGCGCUGAGGGCCUUCCGCGUGCUGCGCCCCCUGCGGCUGGUGUCCGGAGUCCCAAGUCUCCAGGUGGUCCUGAAUUCCAUCAUCAAGGCCAUGGUCCCCCUGCUGCACAUCGCCCUGCUUGUGCUGUUUGUCAUCAUCAUCUACGCCAUCAUCGGCUUGGAGCUCUUCAUGGGGAAGAUGCACAAGACCUGCUACAACCAGGAGGGCAUAGCAGAAGAUGACCCUUCCCCUUGUGCGCUGGAAACGGGCCACGGGCGGCAGUGCCAGAACGGCACGGUGUGCAAGCCCGGCUGGGAUGGUCCCAAGCACGGCAUCACCAACUUUGACAACUUUGCCUUCGCCAUGCUCACGGUGUUCCAGUGCAUCACCAUGGAGGGCUGGACGGACGUGCUGUACUGGGUCAAUGAUGCCGUAGGAAGGGACUGGCCCUGGAUCUAUUUUGUUACACUAAUCAUCAUAGGGUCAUUUUUUGUACUUAACUUGGUUCUCGGUGUGCUUAGCGGAGAGUUUUCCAAAGAGAGGGAGAAGGCCAAGGCCCGGGGAGAUUUCCAGAAGCUGCGGGAGAAGCAGCAGCUAGAAGAGGAUCUCAAAGGCUACCUGGAUUGGAUCACUCAGGCCGAAGACAUCGAUCCUGAGAAUGAGGACGAAGGCAUGGAUGAGGAGAAGCCCCGAAACAUGAGCAUGCCCACCAGUGAGACCGAGUCCGUCAACACCGAAAACGUGGCUGGAGGUGACAUCGAGGGAGAAAACUGCGGGGCCAGGCUGGCCCACCGGAUCUCCAAGUCAAAGUUCAGCCGCUACUGGCGCCGGUGGAAUCGGUUCUGCAGAAGGAAGUGCCGCGCCGCAGUCAAGUCUAAUGUCUUCUACUGGCUGGUGAUUUUCCUGGUGUUCCUCAACACGCUCACCAUUGCCUCUGAGCACUACAACCAGCCCAACUGGCUCACAGAAGUCCAAGACACGGCAAACAAGGCCCUGCUGGCCCUGUUCACGGCAGAGAUGCUCCUGAAGAUGUACAGCCUGGGCCUGCAGGCCUACUUCGUGUCCCUCUUCAACCGCUUUGACUGCUUCGUCGUGUGUGGCGGCAUCCUGGAGACCAUCCUGGUGGAGACCAAGAUCAUGUCCCCACUGGGCAUCUCCGUGCUCAGAUGCGUCCGGCUGCUGAGGAUUUUCAAGAUCACGAGGUACUGGAACUCCUUGAGCAACCUGGUGGCAUCCUUGCUGAACUCUGUGCGCUCCAUCGCCUCCCUGCUCCUUCUCCUCUUCCUCUUCAUCAUCAUCUUCUCCCUCCUGGGGAUGCAGCUCUUUGGAGGAAAGUUCAACUUUGAUGAGAUGCAGACCCGGAGGAGCACAUUCGAUAACUUCCCCCAGUCCCUCCUCACUGUGUUUCAGAUCCUGACCGGGGAGGACUGGAAUUCGGUGAUGUAUGAUGGGAUCAUGGCUUAUGGCGGCCCCUCUUUUCCAGGGAUGUUAGUCUGUAUUUACUUCAUCAUCCUCUUCAUCUGUGGAAACUAUAUCCUACUGAAUGUGUUCUUGGCCAUUGCUGUGGACAACCUGGCUGAUGCUGAGAGCCUCACAUCUGCCCAAAAGGAGGAGGAAGAGGAGAAGGAGAGAAAGAAGCUGGCCAGGACUGCCAGCCCAGAGAAGAAACAAGAGUUGGUGGAGAAGCCGGCAGUGGGGGAAUCCAAGGAGGAGAAGAUUGAGCUGAAAUCCAUCACGGCUGACGGAGAGUCUCCACCCGCCACCAAGAUCAACAUGGAUGACCUCCAGCCCAAUGAAAAUGAGGAUAAGAGCCCCUACCCCAACCCAGAAACUACAGGAGAAGAGGAUGAGGAGGAGCCAGAGAUGCCUGUCGGCCCUCGCCCACGACCACUCUCUGAGCUUCACCUUAAGGAAAAGGCAGUGCCCAUGCCAGAAGCCAGCGCGUUUUUCAUCUUCAGCUCUAACAACAGGUUUCGCCUCCAGUGCCACCGCAUUGUCAAUGACACGAUCUUCACCAACCUGAUCCUCUUCUUCAUUCUGCUCAGCAGCAUUUCCCUGGCUGCUGAGGACCCGGUCCAGCACACCUCCUUCAGGAACCAUAUUCUGUUUUAUUUUGAUAUUGUUUUUACCACCAUUUUCACCAUUGAAAUUGCUCUGAAGAUGACUGCUUAUGGGGCUUUCUUGCACAAGGGUUCUUUCUGCCGGAACUACUUCAACAUCCUGGACCUGCUGGUGGUCAGCGUGUCCCUCAUCUCCUUUGGCAUCCAGUCCAGUGCAAUCAAUGUCGUGAAGAUCUUGCGAGUCCUGCGAGUACUCAGGCCCCUGAGGGCCAUCAACAGGGCCAAGGGGCUAAAGCAUGUGGUUCAGUGUGUGUUUGUCGCCAUCCGGACCAUCGGGAACAUCGUGAUUGUCACCACCCUGCUGCAGUUCAUGUUUGCCUGCAUCGGGGUCCAGCUCUUCAAGGGAAAGCUGUACACCUGUUCAGACAGUUCCAAGCAGACAGAGGCGGAAUGCAAGGGCAACUACAUCACGUACAAAGACGGGGAGGUUGACCACCCCAUCAUCCAACCCCGCAGCUGGGAGAACAGCAAGUUUGACUUUGACAAUGUUCUGGCAGCCAUGAUGGCCCUCUUCACCGUCUCCACCUUCGAAGGGUGGCCAGAGCUGCUGUACCGCUCCAUCGACUCCCACACGGAAGACAAGGGCCCCAUCUACAACUACCGUGUGGAGAUCUCCAUCUUCUUCAUCAUCUACAUCAUCAUCAUCGCCUUCUUCAUGAUGAACAUCUUCGUGGGCUUCGUCAUCGUCACCUUUCAGGAGCAGGGGGAGCAGGAGUACAAGAACUGUGAGCUGGACAAGAACCAGCGACAGUGCGUGGAAUACGCCCUCAAGGCCCGGCCCCUGCGGAGGUACAUCCCCAAGAACCAGCACCAGUACAAAGUGUGGUACGUGGUCAACUCCACCUACUUCGAGUACCUGAUGUUCGUCCUCAUCCUGCUCAACACCAUCUGCCUGGCCAUGCAGCACUACGGCCAGAGCUGCCUGUUCAAAAUCGCCAUGAACAUCCUCAACAUGCUCUUCACUGGCCUCUUCACCGUGGAGAUGAUCCUGAAGCUCAUUGCCUUCAAACCCAAGCACUAUUUCUGUGAUGCAUGGAAUACAUUUGACGCCUUGAUUGUUGUGGGUAGCAUUGUUGAUAUAGCAAUCACCGAGGUAAACAACGCAGAGGAAAACUCCCGCAUCUCCAUCACCUUCUUCCGCCUGUUCCGGGUCAUGCGUCUGGUGAAGCUGCUGAGCCGUGGGGAGGGCAUCCGGACGCUGCUGUGGACCUUCAUCAAGUCCUUCCAGGCCCUGCCCUAUGUGGCCCUCCUGAUCGUGAUGCUGUUCUUCAUCUACGCGGUGAUCGGGAUGCAGGUGUUUGGGAAAAUUGCCCUGAAUGAUACCACAGAGAUCAACCGGAACAACAACUUUCAGACCUUCCCCCAGGCCGUGCUGCUCCUCUUCAGGUGUGCCACCGGGGAGGCCUGGCAGGACAUCAUGCUGGCCUGCAUGCCAGGCAAGAAGUGUGCCCCAGAGUCCGAGCCCAGCAACAGCACGGAGGGUGAAACACCCUGUGGUAGCAGCUUUGCUGUCUUCUACUUCAUCAGCUUCUACAUGCUCUGUGCCUUCCUGAUCAUCAACCUCUUUGUAGCUGUCAUCAUGGACAACUUUGACUACCUGACAAGGGACUGGUCCAUCCUUGGUCCCCACCACCUGGAUGAGUUUAAAAGAAUCUGGGCAGAGUAUGACCCUGAAGCCAAGGGUCGUAUCAAACACCUGGAUGUGGUGACCCUCCUCCGGCGGAUUCAGCCGCCACUAGGUUUUGGGAAGCUGUGCCCUCACCGCGUGGCUUGCAAACGCCUGGUCUCCAUGAACAUGCCUCUGAACAGCGACGGGACAGUCAUGUUCAAUGCCACCCUGUUUGCCCUGGUCAGGACGGCCCUGAGGAUCAAAACAGAAGGGAACCUAGAACAAGCCAAUGAGGAGCUGCGGGCGAUCAUCAAGAAGAUCUGGAAGCGGACCAGCAUGAAGCUGCUGGACCAGGUGGUGCCCCCUGCAGGUGAUGAUGAGGUCACCGUUGGCAAGUUCUACGCCACGUUCCUGAUCCAGGAGUACUUCCGGAAGUUCAAGAAGCGCAAAGAGCAGGGCCUUGUGGGCAAGCCCUCCCAGAGGAACGCGCUGUCUCUGCAGGCUGGCUUGCGCACACUGCAUGACAUCGGGCCUGAGAUCCGACGGGCCAUCUCUGGAGAUCUCACCGCUGAGGAGGAGCUGGACAAGGCCAUGAAGGAGGCUGUGUCCGCUGCUUCUGAAGAUGACAUCUUCAGGAGGGCCGGUGGCCUGUUCGGCAACCACGUCAGCUACUACCAAAGCGACGGCCGGAGCGCCUUCCCCCAGACCUUCACCACUCAGCGCCCGCUGCACAUCAACAAGGCGGGCAGCAGCCAGGGCGACACUGAGUCGCCAUCCCACGAGAAGCUGGUGGACUCCACCUUCACCCCGAGCAGCUACUCGUCCACCGGCUCCAACGCCAACAUCAACAACGCCAACAACACCGCCCUGGGUCGCCUCCCUCGCCCCGCCGGCUACCCCAGCACGGUCAGCACUGUGGAGGGCCACGGGCCCCCCUUGUCCCCUGCCAUCCGGGUGCAGGAGGUGGCGUGGAAGCUCAGCUCCAACAGGUGCCACUCCCGGGAGAGCCAGGCAGCCAUGGCGGGUCAGGAGGAGACGUCUCAGGAUGAGACCUAUGAAGUGAAGAUGAACCAUGACACGGAGGCCUGCAGUGAGCCCAGCCUGCUCUCCACAGAGAUGCUCUCCUACCAGGAUGACGAAAAUCGGCAACUGACGCUCCCAGAGGAGGACAAGAGGGACAUCCGGCAAUCUCCGAAGAGGGGUUUCCUCCGCUCUGCCUCACUAGGUCGAAGGGCCUCCUUCCACCUGGAAUGUCUGAAGCGACAGAAGGACCGAGGGGGAGACAUCUCUCAGAAGACAGUCCUGCCCUUGCAUCUGGUUCAUCAUCAGGCAUUGGCAGUGGCAGGCCUGAGCCCCCUCCUCCAGAGAAGCCAUUCCCCUGCCUCAUUCCCUAGGCCUUUUGCCACCCCACCAGCCACACCUGGCAGCCGAGGCUGGCCCCCACAGCCCGUCCCCACCCUGCGGCUUGAGGGGGUCGAGUCCAGUGAGAAACUCAACAGCAGCUUCCCAUCCAUCCACUGCGGCUCCUGGGCUGAGACCACCCCCGGUGGCGGGGGCAGCAGCGCCGCCCGGAGAGUCCGGCCCGUCUCCCUCAUGGUGCCCAGCCAGGCUGGGGCCCCAGGGAGGCAGUUCCACGGCAGUGCCAGCAGCCUGGUGGAAGCGGUCUUGAUUUCAGAAGGACUGGGGCAGUUUGCUCAAGAUCCCAAGUUCAUCGAGGUCACCACCCAGGAGCUGGCCGACGCCUGCGACAUGACCAUAGAGGAGAUGGAGAGCGCGGCCGACAACAUCCUCAGCGGGGGCGCCCCACAGAGCCCCAAUGGCGCCCUCUUACCCUUUGUGAACUGCAGGGACGCGGGGCAGGACCGAGCCGGGGGCGAAGAGGACGCGGGCUGUGUGCGCGCGCGGGGUCGACCGAGUGAGGAGGAGCUCCAGGACAGCAGGGUCUACGUCAGCAGCCUGUAGUGGGCGCUGCCAGAUGCGGGCUUUUUUUUAUUUGUUUCAAUGUUCCUAAUGGGUUCGUUUCAGAAGUGCCUCACUGUUCUCGUGACCUGGAGUUAACCGGAACAGCGUCUUCAUUCAUUUCUGUUGGGACCAGACGCGGAGCCUGGGUGCGCGAGCCGCCCUCCGGGAGGAAGGCGCCCGGCUGCGUCUGCAGAGGCGGGGAGAGGAGGCGGCGAGGGUCCCGGGGCGCGAGGAAGGCGCCUGCCCUCUCCCAGCUCGCAGGCCCCGGGCCCGGCCGCGCCUCCGCGGGGAGAGCACCCCGGCUUCCCGCGCGCCCUCACCAAAAGGACCCUACAGCAAACGGGUGUCUUUCGACUCUGCUUGUAGAAACCAUUUGCACAUAUUCUGUACGAGCCUCGCUGUCUCCCUAGAGCCAGGGCCCUGCGGAUUUGGAGAAGGGAGCGGGGCAGGACUUCCAGGAGGACCCCAACCCGGCCCGGAGAGGGAGGAGGAGGCCUCCAGGGGCGCGGAGCUCUGGGGAUGGGCGUCGGGCCGGCAGUGGUGCGGCUCACUCCGUCCCUGCCCACCUGCGACGGGAUCCCCCGACCGGCACGGGCCACGCCGAGCUCCCGGCCAGCCGCCGGCCCGCAGGCAGCGCGAGGGAGGAGCUGCGCCGCCGGCUCCGCCCAACCAGGUGGUGCUGAGCUUCCGCUGAGCGCUCUUUUGUUUUGUGGUUUGACACUUUUCUUGACAGCAUGUUGCAGUUUCUUUUCGGUUUUGGUUUUUUUUAAAUGUUUUAUUUUGCUUUCCCAGCGGGAGGGGAGGAAGAAGAGUGUUUACAAAGUCCUGUAGCCCCCUCACCUUUCUGUUUUCACUUUUGCCAAUGUACAUCGGGUUUGGUUUUCUUGUAUUAUUUAAACGGUUGUGGUUUCCUUUUUCCACGGAGGUUCAAUAGAAGCCGCUGCAGGAGAGUUUUACCAACCAUUGUGUAUGCCCAAUAAUUUGUUAUCAUUUCCUUAGGUAGUAACCUAUUUUUGUUCUGGUUUGGUUCGGUUAUCUAAUGGAAAGGUAACUGGCAAUGCACUUGAUGUGGUCUUGCACAUGUGGGUGAUAGAGUUGGGUUCCUUUUUAUGCUGGGUGUACAGGUGGGUUUGGGAGAGAGGAGCAUGCGCGAGAGAGUCUCCGAGUGUGUGCGACGCGUGUGUGUGUGGUGGGUUGUCUGUGUGCAUAUGUCCUGCCCGUGUAUAUGCACCCACACCAUGUGCCCGUGCACACCAGUGACUACGCAGUCCCCCCUUUCUGGUUUAGCUGUGGGAAGAUCUGAAUCUGGGGCCGUUUGAAAGCAAAAACAAACCACUGUCUCUGCUUCUGAAACGGGAAUCAGUAACUCUUUGCAUUUUCUGUCCCACAAGAUAUGCAAAAACAAUGCAAUAAUAUUCAUUUAAAAAUACAAUUGUGAGUUGUGUUGGCAUUAAAACUGUAUUUUAAAAAAAGACAGAAAUUUAAGGGAAAAACACAAGAAGGCAUUUUGCUUCAAUAUAUUCCGUGUAAUGUUUUAUUGCAUUGAUAAUGUUUCUGUUGAAGAAACCGUUAUACUUGAAUUCAGGUCAGUUUCAGUAUUUUUCAAAUAUUUUUUUAAAACUGAAUUGCAAUUGUGCCAAGCGAAUAUAAUGAAUUGAAUUAAGUUGGUUUUCGGAUUCACUUCUUGUAUAUUUUGCUGCAUGUAAAGUAAAUCAUUUUGUAUUUGGAGUGUGACAAGCUUUACCUUUGAACUCAAGUGCUUUUCUAUAUGUGGUUGGGGGAAAGGGAACAAGUUUUCUUUAGUUUGCACAAUGAGCAAAGGUAUCACCAGUGUAGUCAUUAUUCUGCUCUCCACAAACAGGUUUGGACAUUACUGUUUUGCAUAUCUUGUGUUUGCUUACAUUUCCCUCAAUUUUUCCAAAAUCGUUUGCUGGGUAUGUUUGUACCGCCUCUUGCUGUGAGAGACCAGGACCUAUUUUAUUCCAGUCUUCACUCUGUCCACUCUGCUCUGGUCAUCUGAUUUGGUACUUCUCCAAGAACAGCCCUUCACUGUGAGGUGCAGGGAGGCGUUCUGAUGAGCCCUCAGUCACUGGGCCGUCAUCCGCAUCCCCCAUGGAAGAGGUAGCUGGCUUUCCCUUCCCUUCCACCACACGGAAUUUUCUCUUUGGCUUCCUUAGGAAAGUGUACACUAACCGGGAGGAUAAAAUUAAAGUCAGGCUGCUUGGAGGGAGGGGCAUCCUCACUUCCGGAUUCUUGUUGCUCUACCCAACAAGGACAGCAGGGGCUCGAGAAAGGAACUGGUGAAACCCUGAUCCAUCUGAAAGUCAACUCUGCGUGCUCCUUUCUCCAUCCCUUCCUCACUCUGGAGCAGCCUUUCCUUCAGGCUUGCCCUAAUGUUUGGGCUGCCGGGGAGGGGGCCAGGACAAGGGAAGAGGCAUCCGGAGCUCACAGUGGGGGUGGGAACAGAUUUUUGUGGGGGCAUCUCUAAUGCUCACUUAUAUCUCCCUAGAACAUCACUCUUUUGGUGCUGUGUCCUUCAAAUGUAUGUCAACAGUGGUGGCUGAAAAGGGACUGCUUUGGGGAAAACAGGACCCAACCAUUCACCCAGAAUUGACCCAUUAAAUCUCUUCCAGUCCUAGUGUUCCCUGAGCCCCUCUUGGCACAUAUAUAAGUAAGCUAGAAAUUACAAUAAGGGACAGUCCAUUCCUCUAUGACAGCUUGCUGGACUGAUUCAUGACAAAGUGGAGAAAUGUACUCAAUACUCCCCGGUUAACACAGUCUAGAAACAGAGUUUCUUUAUGGAUAUCCACACCCAAGUCAUCCAAACUUUCUUGAUUCCUUUUCACUGCCAUCAAGGUCCUCUAGAAAUUGAGUUUAGGUAUCAUCCUUUGAAAAGUUCCCAAGAUUUCUACCAGGAGGUACACACAGGCGUUCCCUGUCUAGGGCAGGAGGACUAUCCUAGCUUGACCUUCUGAUCCACUAGAAUAAGACUGGCGUAUGAUGCCUGUCAUCAGAACAGACUGGCACAAGUAGUGACAUCAAUGAACCACAGCACAAUCUUCCAAGUGAUGUCUACUCUCCACCUAAAAUGGAAUUUUCCCCAUGACCUUGUAAAACAUAAUUGUCACAUCUUCCAUACCCCUCCUGACAGCCCCCAAGUGUCAGGAGAAAACAGUCAGGGGCUAAGGGCCCAAGGGACUUGAAGAAACAACAGUUUAAGGUCUGCAGUUUGGUCAACUUAAUUCUUGUCCUCCGACCAGCCCUGCCUCUUUCAUUUCCAGACCUUGGAGAAUUUUUCCCAGCUUUGAUUCAGAAGGUACUAGUUAUAACCCCUUUCCUUCUUCUUAAUCCAAUAGGCCUCACUCUCACUGGGAAAUCCACUCAAAGGAACAAGGCAAUGUCUCUCAUUCUAUUUCCCAGUUCCAAAUUCCAGGUGCUUGUCUGGAGUGAAGCUACCCGUUACUUUCUCCCAGCUUUUCUCCACCCAGCAUGUCUCCUGCCCAUGCAGCUGAAGACAGUGGGGCAACCUCAGGAGAAGCAGACCUUUCCAUGCCCAAGUUCAUCUCCUGAGCAACAGUGACACCUAGAAAAUGAGGACUUUGGAAGUCACCCAAAAGAUGGUGGCUACUUUAUGGAGUCCUGAAGAUACACAGCCACCACUCCUAAAGGCAAAGAAAGAAAACACGAAUGUAGGUCAGGGAUAGAGUGGAACCCUGGUCAUCGGGGUUUUUAGCCUCAUCGUGGGAAAGGUGGUAAAGGAGGAUGAUGGCAUCUCCAUCCCUAGAGGCCAAGAAUUGAAAUAUCAUUGUCAAGGAUUAGAAACAAUUCAGCAAAGAGGCCACAAAAAGGGCCUGCUGACUCCCAGAAGACCUCUUUAAACCCCAGGGGAGGCAAAUACUUGCUGAUGGAGUCUGGGCCGUUUCCAUAUUUUAAAGAAGACCUGCCUCUGGGGCAAAUGUCAGCACAGAGAGGACUGGGAGGAGAAUGGAGGCAAGAAAAGGGCAUAUUUUGACUCCCUCUGUGCCUCUUCCCAGUUCAUGGAAGGAUGUGUUCAGCUUACCCACCCACAGUGACCAGUGUGGUGGAGCCGCUGACAUCUCAAGGAUCUAUUUGGGAAGGUGAGAAGAGUACUCAUUCCAUCUGGGGGUGUUGUUCCAGCCACAUCAGCCUACCUGGUGGGAUGUGGGGGUGUCUGCCACCCUGUCCCCCCUCUGCUGAUGUCCCUCCCCUCAGGCUGUCCAGGUGCCACCUGACACAGGCUGCUGUGCAAAGACAGGCGGGGAAGCCCAAACCUCACUCCCAGGGAGGCCCUCAGCCGCCAGAGUCCAGGUUCUCCAGAGGCUACGAUUUGAGGAGGUUGAGGGGGAAGACAGGAGGGAAAGAAAAGUCCUACAACUGUCAGGAAUGGGGCACCUUUCCCUGUCCCUAAGCAAAGCUCCCUCUUCCCACUGCCCUCCCCAGCCCCAGCUCCCUGUCCUCCCCAACACCUAGUGAGAAAGACGGUGCGUGGAAGGGAGUCCCAUGGGCAGAUGCUUACACGACCUCUUUGUGAAGCCUCUUCUGGGUUUAACUUCAUUCAUCAAUUUAUUCUUAUGUCAAAGCAAUGAAACUUUUCUUUCUGGAGCCAGAUACCAAUACAACAGGUGAACGGGUUUCUGCCACAUCUCUACAUUGACGGGGGAUGCUUGAACAACCCCCCUCACUACACAGACACACACCGUUAAGGCACAAGGGCUGGGGUUGAGCUCUAGAUGAGGGACUUUCCUGCUCCUGCAAGGGUGAGCACUGUAUACACAGACAAGGAGGGUGCAGUAGAGUGACUCCCUUGGAUGGAAGUAGUACCAUCAGAACCUACUAUUAUUAUGACAUAAAUUCUAUUUACAUACAUUGAGAGAAUACUACAAUCAACACUUUUUCCUGGGAUGACUUUAAGAGGUUUGAGCCACAGCACCUGAAGUGGCAAAGAUCCAUGGUCUUUGUAGGGUAUUAGAGAACUCUUCCAGUCACCUCUGAAAGCACUCUAGAUCUUGCAGCUGAGUGGAUGAAGUGUAACAAAUCUGUUGCACGCUGAGAGGAGUCAGAAUUAGCAUUUUUCAUGAAAGUUCCCCACGUCUCUACUAAGAAUGAGGAAGAAAAGACUAAGACUAGGUAAUUACACAGAGGCUUGAAAUGUUACAUCACCAGAGCCAAGUCCUCUCCCUUCAGAUCAGUUACUGGCUGCUACACAGGGACACCCCCACCUUUUCAGGGCAUCCCAUGCACUCCACUUCUCAGGAUCUAAGGAAUUUGACUUUGUAGGGAUCCCAGAAAGGGCACUGUGCCACUUCCCCUGGUGUGAAUCAGACAUACAUUGUACAUUCAUUUCUAAAAUUCACUCAUGCACCUCAAACCAAGGUCAUUAUCCAAAAAAAAAAAAAAAAAGCUCUGGGUGGAAGAGUUUGUAAGUUUUAAGAGAGGGUCAUUUCUAUGUGAGGAAAUGCAGAAAUGGACAGAAUGAUUCUUAUUCACUGUUUGGGUCUGGAGAAUUCCCAUUGUGGAAAUCUUAGAGAUCUCAAGUUUAUUACCAAGGGAAUAAGGAAAAAAAGGUGAGCAGGCACCAGGCCAAGCAGUGGCUCCCUUGCCAAGGAACCUGAGGCUGCAGGUUUCAGGGACCCCCUUGAAGAAACCUCUCCUGGCCAUUGGCCAGGAGAAAAGAGAAGUCUCUCCUGUAGAGUCACAAGAGAAGCAAAAGAGGGUGGGUCACUGGGUCCUGGACAUAGCCCCCAACCCCAAGACUUCCCAAUAUGGAGAAACUACACCAAUGUUUAAAAGGGGAAAAGGAAAGAACUUGUACAUCAAGGGAAGAUGAUUUGUAAACACACAGUCCUGUGCAGAAAGAUCCCCUUCAGGAGGUGUCUCCAGCAUCCCAAAGCUGUGCGCACCUUCUCUUUUCCUGCCUCAGGCCACCUAUGCAUCCAGCUGCAGCCCAUACCCACACCUGAAAUCCAUCUCUUGAAUCCCAGCCAGGUUAUAUACCACCCCAUUGCCAUGUCCUGUCCUGGCCAGAAUGCAUGCUGUUCCCCCAAGCCUCGUGGGAGUGAGGCCAUGGGAAACAGAGAUGAGCAUGUCUGGACAAGUCUGUGAUGGUAGUGGAUGAGAAUAACCCAUGGCAAAACACGCACAUUCAUUAAGAAAUAGGGCGACAGAUUCCCCGUUGGUGAAGCACUGAAAGGUCUAUUACUCUCAUAAUAUUGCUGUUUUAUUUUAAUCCACCAGAGCUACCAUGCAAAACUUUCCUCCUGUGAAACGCUCCAGAUAAAGCUCCUCUAAUCUCCCCUUCCCUCAUGUCCUCCAGCUCAAACCCACCUUCAUCCCCCAAACCAAUCUGUAUCAUGCCUGUUAUCAGAGAGGCACAGAAAGAUGGGCAGUGCCUCCGUUGUCACCAUUCCCCACACCCCUACACACCCCCACACCCUCCCCUCCAGGCUCCACGACUUCACAGUCUUACUGUUGUAAAUAUCAUUGUACAGUUUGUAAUCCUCAAAUAAUCCCAUUGUCAGAGGCCUCGCCUGAUGGGCCUUCUCACCCUCGAGAAAGGCCAGGGAAUCUAGAAGGGGCAACCCUUCAAGGAGAGCUUCAGGGUCAUCUCUGUGUGAGACACUAUUGUAUAUUCCUGUAAGAUUGCAUUUUUAUCUAAGGAAUGAUGUUAUUUAAAAAACAAACAAAAAACACAAAAAAUAAGAAUUGCAAAUAAAUUUCUUAACAAUGUCUA